CCCUCCUACGGCGCCCGUGGCUGCAGCGCCAGCGCCAAAGCCAAGUUUGCGCCUCGAGAGUUUGCGCCUCGAGAGUUUGCGCCGGUUCGCAUUCCCCGGCCUCCCGUUCGCUCCCCCGCGAACCAGGCGGCCGUGCGCCUCUCGGGGCAACCACCCAAGAGCACCCGGGCGGGAGGACGCCGAGCAGGGGGUGUUGCGGGCUGGGACAGGGGCAGCCACCUCCCGAAGAUGCAGGAUGGCAGCAGAGCCGCAGCCGUCCAGCCUUUCCUACCGCACCACGGGCUCCACCUACCUGCACCCGCUCAGCGAGCUCCUGGGCAUCCCGCUGGACCAGGUGAAUUUUGUGGUAUGCCAGCUUGUUGCUCUGUUUGCUGCUUUCUGGUUUCGCAUCUACUUACGUCCUGGUACAACCAGCUCUGAUGUCCGGCAUGCGGUUGCCACCAUUUUUGGCAUCUAUUUUGUCAUCUUUUGUUUCGGCUGGUACUCUGUGCAUCUUUUUGUGCUGGUGUUAAUGUGCUAUGCAAUCAUGGUCACUGCUAGUGUAUCCAAUAUUCACAGAUAUUCCUUUUUUGUAGCAAUGGGAUAUCUUACAAUAUGCCACAUCAGCCGAAUAUACAUCUUCCACUAUGGAAUUCUCACUACGGAUUUUUCUGGGCCUCUGAUGAUUGUCACUCAGAAGAUCACAACCUUGGCAUUCCAGGUUCAUGAUGGAUUAGGUCGAAGAGCUGAAGACCUUUCUGCUGAACAACAUCGACUUGCUAUCAAAGUGAAACCCUCUUUUUUGGAAUACUUAAGUUACCUUCUCAAUUUCAUGAGUGUCAUAGCUGGUCCUUGUAACAAUUUCAAGGACUACAUAGCCUUCAUUGAGGGGAAGCAUAUACACAUGAAGUUGCUGGAGGUGAACUGGAAGCGAAAAGGUUUCCACAGCUUGCCAGAACCUUCUCCCACAGGAGCUGUGAUACACAAGUUGGGCAUCACCUUGGUGUCUCUCCUUUUGUUUUUGACGCUAACGAAGACCUUUCCUGUCACCUGCCUUGUGGAUGACUGGUUUGUCCAUAAAGCAAGCUUUCCGGCUCGACUCUGCUACUUAUAUGUUGUCAUGCAAGCCUCAAAGCCCAAGUAUUACUUUGCAUGGACAUUAGCUGAUGCAGUGAAUAACGCAGCUGGCUUUGGGUUCAGCGGAGUGGAUAAGAAUGGGAAUUUCUGUUGGGAUCUGCUUUCGAACCUAAACAUCUGGAAAAUUGAGACUGCCACAAGUUUCAAAAUGUACUUGGAAAACUGGAAUAUUCAGACAGCUACUUGGCUAAAGUGUGUGUGCUAUCAGCGGGUUCCAUGGUACCCCACGGUGCUAACCUUCAUCCUGUCUGCUUUGUGGCAUGGUGUCUACCCUGGAUACUAUUUUACCUUCUUAACUGGAAUUCUUGUCACAUUAGCAGCUAGAGCGGUCAGGAACAACUACAGACAUUACUUCCUUUCUUCAAGAGCUCUCAAGGCUGUGUAUGAUGCAGGCACCUGGGCCGUCACUCAGCUGGCUGUCUCUUACACGGUAGCACCCUUUGUGAUGUUGGCAGUUGAACCGACCAUCAGCUUAUACAAGUCCAUGUACUUUUAUUUGCACAUCAUAAGUCUCCUGAUAAUACUAUUUCUGCCAAUGAAACCACAAGCUCAUACGCAAAGGCGGCCUCAGACUCUGAACUCUAUUAAUAAGAGAAAAACAGAUUGAUACCUCCAAGAGAAGCGGAACAAGCAAAACUGCAGAACGUUCGAAAGAUGAGAUGACAAGGCUUCAAGGGCUCCUCCGGUGGCUUAGAGGCGAUGUUUACAUGCAUCUUUAUUUUGUUCUUUUUUAAAGUGCAGGGAGUAUUUUUUUUUUUUUUUUUUUUUUUUUUUUUUUGAGACGGAGUCUCGCUCUGUCGCCCAGGCUGGAGUGCAGUGGCGGGAUCUCGGCUCACUGCAAGCUCCGCCUCCCGGGUUCACGCCAUUCUCCUGCCUCAGCCUCCCAAGUAGCUGGGACUACAGGCGCCCGCCACUACGCCCGGCUAAUUUUUUGUAUUUUUAGUAGAGACGGGGUUUCACCGUUUUAGCCGGGAUGGUCUCGAUCUCCUGACCUCGUGAUCCGCCCGCCUCGGCCUCCCAAAGUGCUGGGAUUACAGGCGUGAGCCACCGCGCCCGGCCGGGAGUAUUUUUAUAAAGCCUUUUUGUACAGAUUAAUCGGCCAUGUCCAGGUUAUUGGUUUUGAUAUUUUAUAGGACAUUUGAGUGGUGUGGCGAUGUGUAGAGAAUGUGCCAGAGCUGCAGAGACAGUCCAUUCUGGGCUGCUGGCUUUUUGCCCUUCCUGCAUGAUUUCCAGCUACUGUGACCUGGAUGCUGGGAACCCAGGCAUCGGCUCCAAAAAUUAGAAGGCGAGUGCUGAGAAGACUUGUCACAGGUUUCUCAAAUCAGAAUAUACUCAGUCAUAGUGGUUCCCUGGGAAGCCCCAGACCCUUUGACUUGUGACAUUACUGGUUUGCAGACAUAAUAACUACACUCAGAGGACCAUGGAGGCAGAGGGAUCAUGGUUUCAGGGCACUGAAAACUCUACGAGCCAAGAGGACUAGUGCAUGGACUGAAAGUCAGGCAUGCCCUCAAAUAGGCUGUAUUUUCUUUCCAGGAAUGUAACCUUUCCCCUUUUUCUUCUGACCUGAGCCAAGAUUGGAAAUCAGAAAGUCUCCUGUACAUGGAGCUGAAGAGGGGCUGCUGUUUUCCGAAUGUUUUCCAUUUCACAGGCGCCACCUGCUUGCCCGGGGUUGGUCUUGAGAAGACACCCAAAUGUUCAUGCCUCAGAAAGGCAGCAGAAUGCCUUUUAGGAAAUUUUUUUAAAGUAAUUUGAAGUUAUAUAGAAGUUUGGUAAGAAGAAGCAGUUGUUUCUCUCUUUUCUCCCUCAUUUCAUGGAGGUGUUAAUGAUCAUGGCUGGCCGUGAUGUACACAUGGGCUGAUUUUCAUUUUUUCAGUUUCAUAGCUGAGAAAUUCAGCUUUGUUUUAGUUGAAUCAUCAUAUUGGAAAGCAGACAUUGAAAGUUUUCUUUUCUAUCUUUGUUAUGAAUGUGCUAUGGCCCCUUUUGGAGACUUCUAUUGGGUAAUAUUCUAUGUGAGAGAAGGAAACUUGGUAUUAAAUGUUGUGGAAAAUAAUAAUGAUGAUAAUAAUAAAGUAUAUGCUGCAAUGGUGUACUGCCAAUCAGAUUGCUUGGGAGAAGAAAAUUUAUUCAAAUCCAACGAUAAAAAAUUAAUUUCUUAUUGAAUAAACAGUAUGUUCCCAUAUAAAAGAAAUGUUUCUGAUGGGAAUAAUUGCUUUUUGUCUGUGUCAAUAGAGACACAGGUCCAUAAGGUGUCCUACUGCUGCUUCUCUUAGGAUAGUGAAAUGUGAAUGUGAUGUGCCUGUUCCUCUACAGCAUGUAAACAGUCCUGGUGCUGGGGGAGAGUACUAGAACCCAAACUUUAGUCCUUAUUUGGGACAGUGGAAGUUAAGAAGUAGUAGAUGUGAGCUAGUGCAUGAGUCUCACCCCACUUUAACAAGGAAAUCUUGGGGCAACCCUACUUCGCUGUCCCAGGAAGAAUCUUAGAUAGUGGGUAGGGGAAGGGGGUUGUAGGUAUCUAAAAUCUGUCAGAGUUUGUCUCCACCAAGAAUAGUUUGAGGUACGAGACCAAGAAAAAUGUACAUCUUGCAAACUAGCAAAAAUGGUAAAUAUUACCAUUGGUGUGGAGUAUGUGGAAUAAUCAUAUUACAGUGAAGUCUUUGAAUUUACAAUGUGAUUGAUGAUCAGGUUUCACUGUAUGUAAUGUAAGUAUCCUCAUGUCUGAAAGAAGAACUUGGUAAUGAGAGCAGAGGUGUCUGCUUUGGUGACCAGCUGCCCUGGUUUGCCAAGGACUCUCUCAAGCCCUCAGUCCUGGGCAAGCUGGGGCCAUUGGUCCCACUAGUGACUGCCCAGAAUUGAUUACUCCUUAUGGGAUGAGGAGAAGUCAAACCUCUAGGAGUUGAGCUUAUGGAUGCUAUAUGUCAGACUUGGUGUUAGGCCCUGGGACACAAACAUGAGGCUUUAUUCUGUAUAAAAAGAACAACACAUAGGAGACUGAUUAGCAUCCUUUUUCUUCUGAAAACCACUUACCCAUAGAAAAAGAUUUCAACUGAGGACCAACAUUUAGACGGAAGGUUGGGACUGUUUUUAUUACCUUAGAUUUCCAAGUUGUCCUAAAUAUAAGAUGCAGUUCAUAAAUACUUAUUGGAAUGUGAGCUUUCAGUUGAAAAUAAAUACACUUUCUGGUUUUGUUUUUGAAAAAGCCAAAUCUAAAA